ACUCGUGUGCGCGCUCGUCCGCCCGCCAGUCCUCUCAACGCGCGCUUGGCCGCCCGACGACGCGGGAGCCGCACGCGCCGGACGAGGCUCGCUGCGCUCCCUGUUGCCCAGCGCGGGCCCGUUGAGGCGGAGCCCUCAGUUCCCGGCCAGGACACGGUCUGGGCCGCCGAAUCUCCGGCCGAAGAGCGGCGGCGGCAGCGGCGGGAAAAAAAUGAAGAAUGAAAUUGCUGCCGUUGUCUUCUUUUUCACAAGGCUAGUUCGAAAACAUGAUAAGUUGAAAAAAGAGGCAGUUGAGAGGUUUGCUGAGAAAUUGACCCUAAUACUUCAAGAAAAAUAUAAAAAUCACUGGUAUCCAGAAAAACCAUCGAAAGGACAGGCCUACAGAUGUAUUCGUGUCAAUAAAUUUCAGAGAGUUGAUCCUGAUGUCCUGAAAGCCUGUGAAAACAGCUGCAUCUUGUAUAGUGACCUGGGCUUGCCAAAGGAGCUCACUCUCUGGGUGGACCCAUGUGAGGUGUGCUGUCGUAGAGAUGGGGUUUCACCAUGUUGGCCAGACUGCUCUCAAACUCCUGACCUCGUGAUCCGCCCGCCUUGGCCUCCCAAAGCGCUGGAUUACAGGCGUGAGCCACUGCGCCCGGCCUCCUCCUUUUUGAUUAUGUA